AUUCUAGUGCAGCCCUGGUUACGCCUCCUCUGGCUCAGUCACACAGCGACGUAGAGGUGACUGGAGGUAUAUACUUGUCCUCACCUGGAUCAUGCUGAUGUGGCCCCAACCCCACCUCCCUACCCAUCCCCACCUCCCUACCCAUCCCCACCUCCCUACCCAUCCCCACCUCCCUACCCAUCCCCACCUCCCUACCCAUCCCCACCUCCCUACCCAUCCCCACCUCCCUACCCAUCCUAUGAUGUCCAAAGAAACCAGACAGAGCAAAUUGGCCGAGGCCAAGGAACAGUUGACAGACCAUCAUCCCCAGACCAACCCUAGUGUUGGUACAGCAGCAAGCGACACCAAAAAGAAGAAAAUAAAUAAUGGCACUAACCCUGAGACAACCACUUCUGGUGGUUGCCACUCGCCUGAGGAUGAACAGAAGGCAAGCCACCAACAUCAGGAAGCCCUAAGGAGGGAGCUAGAGGCCCAGGUUCAUACCAUACGAAUCCUUACAUGUCAGAAAACUGAGCUUCAGAUGGCACUCUACUACAGCCAGCAUGCUGUCAAGCAGUUGGAAGGAGAGGCCAGGGAUCUGAUCAGCCGCCUGCAUGAUUCAUGGAAGUUUGCAGGAGAGUUAGAGCAGGCUCUCUCUGCUGUCGCUACACAGAAGAAGAAGGCGGAUAGGUACAUUGAGGAGUUAACAAAGGAGAGGGACGCCCUGAGUCUGGAACUGUACAGGAACACCAUAACUGAUGAGGAGCUGAAGGAGAAAAAUGCCAAACUACAAGAAAAACUUCAACUUGUAGAAUCUGAAAAGUCUGAGAUCCAGCUCAACGUAAAGGAGCUAAAAAGGAAACUGGAGAGGGCCAAGCUCCUGCUGCCACAGCAGCAGCUGCAGGCGGAGGCUGACCACCUGGGUAAGGAGCUGCAGAGUGUGUCAGCAAAGCUCCAAGCCCAGGUGGAAGAGAACGAGUUGUGGAACCGCCUGAACCAGCAACAGGAGGAGAAGAUGUGGAGGCAGGAGGAGAAGAUACAGGAGUGGGAGGAGAAGAUACAGGAGCAGGAGGAGAAGAUACGGGAGCAGGAGGAGAAGAUACGGGAGCAGGAGGAGAAGAUGCGGAGGCAGGAGGAGAUGAUGUGGGAGAAGGAGGAGAAGAUGCGGAGGCAGGAGGAGAUGAUGUGGGAGAAGGAGGAGAAGAUGCGGAGGCUGGAGGAGAUGAUGUGGGAGAAGGAGGAGAAGAUACGGGAGCUGGAAGAGAAGAUGCACGAGCAGGAGAAGAUACGGGAGCAGGAAGAGAAGAGGCAGGAGGAGGAGAAGAUACGCGAGCAGGAGAAGAGGCAGGAGCAGGAGGCGAAGAUGUGGAGGCAGGAGGAGAAGAUACGGGAGCAGGAAGAGAAGAUACGGGAGCAGGAGAAAAAGAUGUGGAGGCAGGAGGAGAAGAUUCACGAGCAGGAGAAGAUACGGGAGGAGGAGAAGAGGCAGGAGCAGGAGGAGAUGUGGAGGCAGGAGGAGAAGAUAAGGGAGCAGGAGGAGAUAUGGAGGCAAAAGGAGAAGAUGCACGAGCAGGAGAAGAUACGGAAGCAGGAGGAGAAGGUGUGGAGGCAGGAGGAGAAGAUGCACGACCAGGAGGAGAAGAUACGGGAGCAGGAGGAGAAGAUGUGGAGGCAGGAGGAGAAGAUAAGGGAGCAGGAGGAGAAGAUACGGGAGCAGGAGGAGAAGAUACGAGAGCAGGAGGAGAUGAUGCAGGAACAGGAAGAGAAGAUGGGGGAGCAGGAAGAGAAGAUGCAAGAACAGGAGAAGAUGCGGAGGCAGGAGGAGAAGAUAAGGGAGCAGGAGGAGAAGAUACGGGAGCAGAAGGAGAAGAUACGAGAGCAGGAGGAGAAGAUAUGGGAGCAGGAGGAGAAGAUACGAGAGCAGGAGGAGAUGAUGCAGGAACAGGAAGAGAAGAUGUGGGAGCAGGAGGAGAAGAUGUGUGAGCAGGAAGAGAAGAUGCAAGAACAGGAGGAGAAGAUGCGGAGGCAGGAGGAGAAGAUGUGGGAGCAGGAAGUGAGGCUGCGGCAGCAGGAGGAGAAGAUGCAGGAACACCAGGAGCACCUGGAAGCUGCCAUCUAAUGAGCACAUGACAAGAAGGCAAAGACAAUAAACAUGUAAAAGCCGGCAGCAAGGCCUGGAGAAGAGUAAGCCGCCAUGUGACUGUUUAGAAUAUAGUCUGAGCACAAACCUGAAAAAAAAAUUUUAUUUAUUUUAAAUUGUGGCAAAAUACUGGCCAGGCAUGGUAGCUCACGCCUGUAAUCCUAGCAAUUUGGGAGGCCGAGGUAAAUGGAUGACCUGAGGUCAAGAGUUCAAGACCAGCCUGGCCAAUACAAAAAUUAGCCGGGCAUGGUGGCGCAUGCCUGUAAUCCCAGCUACUUGGGAGGCUGAGGCAGGAGAAUCGCUUGAACCUGGGAGGCAGAGGUUGCAGUGAGCUGAGAUCGUGCCACUGCACUCAAGCCUGGGUGACAGAGCGAAACUCCGUCUCAAAAAAAAAAGUUUCUUCCUUACAUGUAUGUUUCUAUUAGUUUUCUUCUUGGUCUUUCUCAUUUAGUCUUGUGUUGUCUUUUGACAUUCAUAGUAAACUUUUAUCUGCCUCCAGAGAGUAUUGACUUUGAGUUUAUGGCACACAAUUGGAGUAAGGGCAGAUCGCCUUCAUCUACUUUGGGACUAAGCUGGUUCAAAGCAGGUUUUAGGUUUUCUGAUGGCUGGUCUAUGUUUUAUUCAUUUGGACUCCCAGGGGUGGCCCUUCCAGGGUCCCCACCAAGGUCCCAUCUCCUUCCUGGGACCCAAAUUCUCAUUAGGUCAUUUCAGCCCUGUGAGAGUGCCAAACAUUCAGCUAGGCUCUCCAGCCUCUUAACUACCACUUCAUACUCAGUUUCUUAGCCUCUUAGCCCUCUACUGUUGACCAAUCACCAAAUGUGGGAAAGCACUACAGACUGUCAGGAUCACCUCCUAGGCCUGGUCACUCAAGUCCUGACUGAGGUCUCCAAUUACCUUCCAACAAUUGUUUUUGAUUGGGGGCGGGGCACAUUUUUAUCCAGUUUUUCUAACUGCUCUUGUGGGGAGGCGAAUCUGUAACAAGCUCCUCUGCCUUUACUGAAAGUUGAAAACCUUCAUCUGUCCUUUUUUUGUUGUUGUUGAGAUGGAGUCUUGCGCUGUUGCCCAGGCUCUAGUGCAAUGGCACGAUCUCUGCUCACUGUAACCUCUGCCUCCUGGGUUCAAGCAAUUCUCCUGCCUCAGCUUCCCGCGUAGCGUGUGCCACCAUGCCUGGCUAAUUUUUUUUUAUACCUUUAAUAGAGGCAGGAUGUCACCAUGUUUUCCAGGCUGGUCUCGAGCUCCUGACUCAGGUGAUCUACCUGCCUCAGCCUCCCAAAGUGCUGGGAUUACAAGUAUGAGCCACUGCAUCCGGCCCAUCUGUCUUUUAAAACAUGUUUUUAAUUGGAGGUAUAAUUUCUAUUAGUGAAAUGCACAGGUCUGGUUUACAUUUUGAUGAGUUUUAACUCAUUUAACAUUACUAUGGAACCCACCUCCUUUGAAGAUACAGAGUAUUUCUAUCAUCCAGAAAGUUCUCCUGUGCUUUCAUGCUGUCCCGCACUCCCCCAGCAGCUGAUGAACAUGCUGAGGACAUUGGUACUGGAUUCUGGCCGCCCCAAAAGAGCCGCUUUGACCAGGCUUACCCAGCACUAAAUCCCUGCCUGCUCUCUCAAAAUUUCCAUCUUUAAACUGGUUGUACCUAUAACCCUCCCUCAUCAAGUCAAUAGAUAAACAAACCCUGAAAAAUAAACAACUCUUCCUGGCCCAGC